ACAUUCCCGGGCCAGCUUCUGUACUGCCAGGUCCGGGUCGGCGGCUGCACUGCGGAUGAGACCGGUGCGACUCAUGAAGGUGUUCGUCACCCGCAGGAUACCCGCCGAGGGUAGGGUCGCGCUCGCCCGGGCGGCAGACUGUGAGGUGGAGCAGUGGGACUCGGAUGAGCCCAUCCCUGCCAAGGAGCUAGAGCGAGGUGUGGCGGGGGCCCACGGCCUGCUCUGCCUCCUCUCCGACCACGUGGACAAGAGGAUCCUGGAUGCUGCAGGGGCCAAUCUCAAAGUCAUCAGCACCAUGUCUGUGGGCAUCGACCACUUGGCUUUGGAUGAAAUCAAGAAGCGUGGGAUCCGAGUUGGCUACACCCCAGAUGUCCUGACAGAUACCACCGCCGAACUCGCAGUCUCCCUGCUACUUACCACCUGCCGCCGGUUGCCGGAGGCCAUCGAGGAAGUGAAGAAUGGUGGCUGGACCUCGUGGAAGCCCCUCUGGCUGUGUGGCUAUGGACUCACGCAGAGCACUGUCGGCAUCAUCGGGCUGGGGCGCAUAGGCCAGGCCAUUGCUCGGCGUCUGAAACCAUUCGGUGUCCAGAGAUUUCUGUACACAGGGCGCCAGCCCAGGCCUGAGGAAGCAGCAGAAUUCCAGGCAGAGUUUGUGUCUACCCCUGAGCUGGCUGCCCAAUCUGAUUUCAUCGUCGUGGCCUGCUCCUUAACACCUGCAACCGAGGGACUCUGCAACAAGGACUUCUUCCAGAAGAUGAAGGAAACAGCUGUGUUCAUCAACAUCAGCAGGGGCGACGUCGUAAACCAGGACGACCUGUACCAGGCCUUGGCCAGUGGUAAGAUUGCAGCUGCUGGACUGGAUGUGACGAGCCCAGAACCACUGCCUACAAACCACCCUCUCCUGACCCUGAAGAACUGUGAUUCCUUCACUUGUCCCUCACCAAGGACGGGACAAACAGAACCCAGUUGUGACCAUGGCACUUGAAUCUUGAUACCUAGACCAUCAGGAAAAUUAAGGAGCACUUCCAGAAAAGGAGUUAACUGGAAGAAAUGAGAACUAGGUAAGGACGUAACUCUUAUUUUGGUCAGAACGAUUAGAGGUAGGUGGGUUUAAUUUUAAAAUUAGUUUCAGCACCUACACAUAUUGUUCCCUUUGCCCAUUCUGUCCCCCCAGCCCCUCCCUGCCCCCAGGUGGAUUUUUUUUUUUUUUAAUCACCACCUUACCCACUUCUCUCCAAGGUCAGGCCACAGCACUGCCAUUGCCAAUGCCUUGCUCUGUGCUCAAGGAAUCAGCUUCCAGCUCUUCCCAGCAGCCAAGCCAAACUGGCAGAUGGAGUUUCCAACUUGGGAGGCAGGUCCAGGGAGCAGCACAAGAUUACGCAGGCCCUCAGAGAGCAACUGGGUAGACUGAAAAGCAAAAUCUCAUGCAUGUGCGUAGCUCAAAGACAGAAAAGGCGGGGGAAGGCAGAAGGGAAUGAUUUGAGAGGAACGACCAAUUAACUGUUAAUAGAAGGUUUGGUUUAAAACAAAGUACUAGUCAAAGAAGGGCUGGCAAAGAGAUAUUACCCUCUUUGGUUUCAACCUUAAUAACGUAAAGAAAAAGAACACAUAUUUAGAGGCAUGAAUAUGACAAAUUUUUUAUUUCAAAAAUCUCAAGUUGUAACCAGCAUAGCACCACUGACAUGGAUGCCUUGAUAGAACUCCUUGAUAGAACUUUAUGAUCUGUUCACCAGAAAAGAUUCUACAUGAUCACGCCAGACUAUAAUUAAGGCUAACCAAUCAAAAUUCAGGUACCCAAAACCAGUUAUAAUCCAGGUAGAAACUACAGAUCAUAGGAACCCUGGGACUGGUUUUCCAGGGAACCCUGGAAUUAUUUUUUAAGUGCUACAGCAUGUACAAGGACACUGGCCCACAAGCUUGCUUCUCACACGUAGAAACUGACAGACUAAGAGGUAGAUGAGAGAUUCCAGGUUCCAUCUAGCAGUGGAGAGGCAGGGCUCCAGCAUGUAUCAGAGAUAAGCCCCAAAAGCAAAGUCCACUUAUGCUUCAGCAGAGGUAAGCGGGCAGGCUCCUGGCACCACCUCCUCCAAAUGGAAGGGAAGGAGGGCUGCACCGCUCUGCCUGUGUCACUGGCUCCUCUCCCUGGGUCCAGGCAGGGCCUCUCAUUUUCUCCAGGCUAACCCACUGUGUCCCAAGGUUAAUCUCACAAGACACUGGUCCCUACAUCAUGUAAAGGGUGGAUGGGGAGCCUCCUAACACCAUGUCAACAUGACUGCUAACAAGGAGCCACACACACAACUGAAUUUCACAGGACCUCAUAUCCUCCAAUGGGCUCUUUCCCACAUCUACUCGAAAGGAAUCGUGGGUUUCCCUUUGGGCUUUUCUUCCUGGGAAUCAGUCCAUGGGAGAUGCCAAGCGCCCCUGGAACAUGAAAUUAUCCACACAUGUGUAACUGCACACUCUAGAUUAACAGGAGAGAAAACACGCUCAUUUUUGUUUCCAGCUACACAUACUUAGCUUUCUAAACACAAAAACUGAAUAAUUUAUCUGAUUUAUGAAUGAUGGUUUGGUAUGUCUAAGAAAGCUAUAUAAAACAUAAAAUGAACUCAUGUUCAUGCAUGAAUUAAACUGACUUCAUGAGUUCUAGGGAGACGCAUUAACCUGUGCUGUUCCCCUGGACGCACACUUGGCCUCAUACAGGUGCCACUAACAGCCCUGAUGGCAGUGUCAGAGGACAGCAAGGUGAGGCUGGGGAAGUGAGGCUGUAGGGCCCAGAGAGGCCCUAGUGCCUCCAACAGUCUCAGAUGCUACUUGAUUACUUCUAUGCUAUGGGCUGCUAACUCUUACAUAGCCUAGAAAAUAUUUACCCAUGAACACUACCAUGUUUGGAUUUCAAACAACUUUAAACAUUUGGUAUCAGAUUGGGGGAGCAACAAAUAAUAAAAUUUAGGGUCUGUACUGUUAAAAGUAUAGUAUAUAACAGUAAUAAAACCUGUGUGGGGCA